CUCUUUGUGUGGUGCCCAGAUAGGGGAGCGGAGGUGGCGGCGGCGGCGGUAGCGGUGGCCUUGGUUGUCUUCCAGUCUCCUCGGCUCGCCCUUUAGCCGGCACCGCUCCCCUUCCCUCCCCCUUCCUCUCUUCCUUCCUUCCCUCCCCUUCCCUUUUUCCCUUCCCCGUCGGUGAGCGGCGGGGGUGGCUCCAGCAACGGCUGGGCCCAAGCUGUGUAGAGGCCUUAACCAACGAUAACGGCGGCGACGGCGAAACCUCGGAGCUCGCAGGGCGGGGGCAAGGCCCGGGCCUUGGAGAUGGAGAAUUCUCAGUUGUGUAAGCUGUUCAUCGGCGGCCUCAAUGUGCAGACGAGUGAGUCGGGCCUGCGCGGCCACUUUGAGGCCUUUGGGACUCUGACGGACUGCGUGGUGGUGGUGAAUCCCCAGACCAAGCGCUCCCGUUGCUUUGGCUUCGUGACCUACUCCAAUGUGGAGGAGGCGGACGCCGCCAUGGCCGCCUCGCCCCAUGCCGUGGACGGCAACACUGUGGAGCUGAAGCGGGCGGUGUCCCGGGAGGAUUCGGCGCGGCCCGGUGCCCACGCCAAGGUUAAGAAGCUCUUUGUCGGAGGCCUUAAAGGAGACGUGGCUGAGGGCGACCUGAUCGAGCACUUCUCGCAGUUUGGCACCGUGGAAAAGGCCGAGAUUAUUGCCGACAAGCAGUCCGGCAAGAAGCGUGGAUUCGGCUUCGUGUAUUUCCAGAAUCACGACGCGGCAGACAAGGCCGCGGUGGUCAAGUUCCAUCCGAUUCAGGGCCAUCGCGUGGAGGUGAAGAAAGCAGUCCCCAAGGAGGAUAUCUACUCCGGUGGGGGUGGAGGCGGCUCCCGAUCCUCCCGGGGCGGCCGAGGCGGCCGGGGGCGCGGCGGUGGUCGAGACCAGAACGGCCUUUCCAAGGGCGGCGGCGGCGGUUACAACAGCUACGGUGGUUACGGCGGCGGCGGAGGCGGCGGCUACAAUGCCUACGGAGGCGGCGGCGGCGGUUCGUCCUACGGUGGGAGCGACUACGGUAACGGCUUCGGCGGCUUCGGCAGCUACAGCCAGCAUCAGUCCUCCUAUGGGCCCAUGAAGAGCGGCGGCGGCGGCGGCGGUGGAGGCAGUAGCUGGGGCGGUCGCAGUAAUAGUGGACCUUACAGAGGCGGCUAUGGCGGUGGGGGUGGCUAUGGAGGCAGCUCCUUCUAAAAGAAAAUUUAAAAUGCCUGGGAGUGGCUAUAGGGGUAGCUCUUUCCAACAGCCCAAGUGGGGUCAACUCCUAAGCCCCACCCCCUCACACACACCGCCUUCCCUGUUUUGCCCUUGGGGGAGCCACUUCUAAGGCUGCUUACCCUUGGGGGUGUUCCUCUAUUUGCCUGCCACCUCUCUUGUCUCUCCCUCUGAAGAUGGACUCGGCCCCACAUACACAUUUUUGUGUUACAGUCAUUGAUGGACUCUAUUUUUUUAUUAUUACUUGGACCUUGGUCGUUUUUAUACUAGCAAAAUGUCUUGUUUUAAUUUGUGUUUUUUGGGGGGAGGGAGGGAGUGAACUUGCUGAUUCUGUAGCAAAACCUGGGUGGGGGUUGGGGUGGGGGGUAGUUUACUUUGUUGUAAGGACUUGAUAACCUGGCUACAGCGUUUUCUAUGAAAUCUACUUGGAUCCCAUGCCUGAAAUUUGGAAGCAUAUGUACAAAAAUCAUUUUUACGUUUUAUUUUUAAUAAAUCAUUGUGUUUGACCGUACAUGUCUAACAUUUUUUUUCUAGGAUCCAUUCCGUACCGUUUUUUAAGGGAUAUUUGUUUAAGACUUUACGUGUUAAUUCUUUAUUCUUGAUGUGUACUUAGAGAAACUUAAGAGGUCCUGUGGUUUUUUUCCCCUCUCCUGUUGCCCUGCUAGUUGCGUGUUGAAUUAUAUCCCUUACAGGCAAAACUUUUGAAGUGGUGGAUGUGGCUUUUUAAACUCUUAAGUUUCUGUGCAUCCAUCUCUUGUACUAAGCGAAUUGUUUAUCAUCUUGACAUGGUUGGUCAUUUCUAUGACAAUUUACUUCAAACUGUGUACUGUGUAGUUCUAUAUAGUUUGUGUUAAGCAUGUCAUUCAUAUAAACUGUUUAAAAUUUUUCAGAUGGCCUAGUUUCAUCCCUCUUACUGGUUUGUCUGUAAUGAAUGGUUAAAAAUAAGGGUUAUAUUUUACCCUCAAAUGCGUUUUUGUACUUUCAGAGCAGGUUUAAACGUUUUUUUUUUUUUUUUCCUAUAUCCGAACUGUUGGCCUCAUGGAAAUCCCUUUCCCGAUCUUUGUAGCACCAUCUACUGGCAGAAUGGCAGAGUAGCUGCGAAACAAUUUGUUUAAAAACUUGCUUAAGACAAUUGCAUCAGAUUUGGAAGUUUUGCCAUCAAAAUUCUUUGCAGAAUUGGAAGUUAACACAUUUGCUUGUAACUGAGAUGGGCUUCACAGGAAUGUAGUUGCCAGUUCAUAUCACAAUAGCCCUUUCUAUAUGAGGUUUGAAAAUGUAAACUGCUAUGCAUAGCUUGGGCAAUAGCCCUAAAUUGCUAUGACAACUAAUGAACCAGCUACGUAUACUGGUAUUUUAGGUGCAAGUUGUAAAGCAAAAUAUCUGUGUAUUCUGCUUGGUUAACAAAUGUAUAUUUGUAGCCCUUUCCUGCAAUAGCAUUCAAGUUGUUGUUUAUAAGAGAAGAACAAAAGUGAUAAUAGGUGAAAAUUGCCUUUCUGGAUAGAAAUAGAGAAUAGCAACGUUUAUGGAUAUCACAAAUAAAGAAUUCAAUUCUUUACAUGAUUGAGUGAGAGUAUGUAUAACCUGGUGGGUGGGUUCAGAGUACCUUUUAAUCUAGUAUGCUUAACUUGAUGUUAAUAUUUAACUUAAAUAUUUGACUUACAUGUUGACGUUGAAGGCUCAAAGCUAUACUAAGAAGCUUUCUGAAAGAUUGGGCUUUAAAAUAAAAUAAUAUUUUAAUAUUGAACCAUUUUUUAACUUCUUGUCACUGUUCAAUUCCUAAGGUCUAGUUCUUGCCAGUUUUUUUUUUUUUUUUCCUGAUUGGCAGGGCUUUUAAAGAAGUAAGAAGAAAGGUUAAGAUUAUUAGGCUAGGUUAUAGCUGCUCAGUAGUCAUUUUGACAAAGGGUAGCGGAUGGUUGGUACAAAUAGUGUUAUAUCCUCUAUGACAAACGGGGUGGAUGUUUUUACACAUUGAGGUAAUACAUAGUCAAAUCCUUUGCUCUCAAAUAGUUGUACACUUUCCAUACAUUUCUGUCUUAUUUUUUAAUUCUAGUGAUACACAAAUUACAUGUGGGCUACUUCAUUUGGUAAUUUGGUCCAGCUUUUUGGUGGCUGUAGAGUGGCCUCUAGGAUACAGAAAAUGAUUCUCUGAAAUUUUUCGUUGUAAUUGUUAAAUACUACUCUGCUUGACUUACUCAGUUUUGGUGGGAAGAUCUGGGUCAAUUGGAAUAGUACACCUUUCUCAGGGUUUUCAGUUUAAUAAGGUUGUCAUAUUAUUCCCAACAUGGGAAUAUAGUGGCUUCUAAAGUUUGCAAAUGAAUUAUGUAAAAGGAUUUUCUGUGUAUUAGGAAGGCAACCUGUUCUGUUCAUGGUAUAUUAACACUUCAUUGUCAUGUGUCUACCCUUAAAAUUGCUAUUUGUAGUGAAGAAAAAAGCAUAGUGGUAUUUAGUCACUUCUGGGUUCCUCUUGUCAGUUUAUAUGCAAACAUUUUGGCAUGUGGGACUUGGGGAGGAGGGACAAUUGGUUGUAUGUUUUGACCACUUCCACCUAUGAAAAUUAUCUGAACAUUAUUCAGAUUUAAGAGUUCAUGGGAGCAGGUGGUACAGAACCUAGUGUUGAAUAUAAUUUUUGUGCCAUGCUUGAAUGUAUUUUGACGGAUUAGCAAAAUAAAAGUGAACCUCCUAUUUUUCAUCUUAAUGUGAAGAUCUUUGGCAUUUACAUUCUUUUAAAAGUAUAAAUUCAGUAGUCAUUAGUUGAAAGUGGUUUGAAAGGCUGUUAGAGAUGAUACAGGUUGAGUAUUCCUUAUCUGAAAUUCUUGGGCCCAGAAGUGUUUUGAGUUUUAGAUUUUUUUCAAUUUUUGAAUAUUUCCAUUAUGUUUACCAGCUGAGCAGCUCUCAUACAAAAAUGUAAAAUCCAAACUGCUUCAAUGAGCAUUUCCUUUGAAUGUCAUGUCUGCACUCAAAAAAUUUCGGAUUUUGGAGCAUUUUAGAUUUUUUGAUUGGAAUAUCUGUAGUGUUUUUCAGGUCAUUUAAAAAGCUCUCAUUGGUACUGAUUUACUGUAUCCAAAAAAAAGCCUGCAAGUGGUUAAGGUUCACAGUGAUAACUAUCAAAUCAGAAUGACUAUACUGAUUGUACCCAUUCAUCCAUUUUUAACUUAGUGAUUUGGAACGUUUCAUAUUCAAAUCUAAUUUUCAUAAUUUUUAAGUAAACCUAAAAGAUUGAGGAUACUUGAGAAAUUUGCAUUUAUGAUUUCCUUCAAAACCAGAAGUGAUGGUAUCAGUUAUUGGAUUUGUAAACUUAGUUUACCUUUUAAGUGUGCUUAAGUUUUGAGAGUUUGCAUUUUAGGUUAAAUUUUGUCUGCCCGCGUCUGCUGAUUGCAGAUAGGCAUUUGGAUGUUGGAUUUGGAGCAGAACUGCAUCUAGACUACACGGAUUUUACCCAAAAAGACAGCACUUGCACUUAGGCUAAGUGUCUUUCUCCAUCGUAACCAAUUUAUUGAAUCACUUUAAGAGUGAUCAUUGGGGAAAUUUUCCUCCUCAGCCUUAUUUUGGCCUUUUGAAACAGCAACAAAGACUGCCUAGUCAAAUAACUCCUUAGCUGUCCUGCUUUUGAGUGAACUUCAUAUUUGCCUUGAAUGAGAAUUUAAAUGUUACAAGGUAAAACAUUUAUUAUAAAAAGAUAUUUGAAAGCUGCUAUUUAAAAAGGAAUUCCAAAGUAGGAAGACUAGAAGGGCAAUUCUCUAUUUUCCACCUAUUUUUUUUACUUUGAUUUGAAGCCAGAUGAUUUGAACCUUCAGAGAGGGAAAGGAUUCAGGAAGACACCUUUGGUAGUUAUUCUUAACUGUUUCCUUCUCUAUUCAGGCAGGCUUUCUUUGUCUCUUUAAUUCUUUUACCACUUUGUAUGGUUUACUUAAAAAAUCUAUCUGAAAUAGCUAUCAUUUCCUGCUAUAAAGUUCUCAAGUGUAAACUUUUGCCAUUUAAACAGUGUGCUUAUUUCCCAGUGUUUACCGUCAAUUUCAUUGGGUGUUAGGCACCUUUGUGUAAGACAGUUCUAUAAUGUGGAGGUACACAGCAGUGAGACAAACAUGGUUGCUGUCUUCAUAUACCUUGCGUUCUGGUUGGAAUUCAAUUUAUUUUGAAAUGGGAAUUCAAUUUAUUUUGAGAUGAUGCAUCUUUUCCUUUACAGCAUUGUGUCACAAUCUCAUAUUGUUCACACCAUCAAAAUUGGAGUUAGCUCCAUUGUCAUUGAAUGUACAUUCUCUGAUGAAAAUUAAGACUCUUUUCUCCUUAAUUGAUUACUUUUUAGAAAUCAAAGGUGUAUUUUGUCUUUGAUGCUUACGUUGCAAAUGUAAUUUGCUUCAUAGUGGGUAUCUGAUUUAAUAUUUCAUAGCCCUUAAGGACGUAAAUUUGGGCAUCCAAUAGACCAAAUUCUGUUCCUGACACAGUCACUUUCUAGCACUGCGACCUUGGACAAACUGGCCCGAGCCUCACUUGCCUUAUUUGUAAAAAAAUAGGCUAUGGUAAUACCUGCUACAUAGGAUUGUUGGGCAGAUUCAGUGAAAGAAUGCAUAUAAAGAAGGGCUUACUGUAGUCUCUGGUACACAGUAAUUUUACUAUAUGGCCCCUAAUGAAGAGGUGGGACAGACUAGCAAAAGGCAUACUUUUAUAUCUUAGUACCCGAGAUAUGCAUGGUCUUUAGGCUUUGCUCUUUACUUGCUGGGUGAGCUUCCAUGUGGUAGUUCUCUAAAUCACUGCUGCUUCAACUCUAGUAGGAGAGAGAUGAAUUCUGCUAGCCAUCUGUAAUGUUUUAAGUAUUUGUUAAUAUUAGGAAGGUAUAAAUAAUGUGAGUGUUGAGGAGAGGUGACUUCAGGUAGGAAGAAGGAUCAAGAGAGGCAUUGUGGAGCAUAUAACAUUUAACCUUAAAAGAUAGGUCUUAUAGAGAAGGUGGGAGGAGAAAGAGGGCAUUUUAGGUGGAGGACAGAUAGGCAGAAACAUGGAGCGUAUUUGGAGAAGUAUGCAUAUUGGAUGCCAAACACUAGGUACAUUUACAAAUGUUCUCAUUGCAUCAUUCAGUAACCUUCACAGAUAAGGUUGCUAAAUCUCAUGCCAGAAAAGUAACUCCCAAGGACCCCCAGCUGGUGACAUGGUAGAACUGAGAGUUGAAUCCAAGUUUGACCAAUUCUAGUUGUUUCGCUCCUUCUACUAAGCUUCAUUGACUUCCAGCUAACAAAUGUCUAAUUUGUACUAAGAUAAAAGAGAGUUGUGAGAAAUAAAUUGAGAAAAUGAAGUUGGAACCAGGUUACUGAGGUCUUUGAGUAGUAGGCUAAGGAGUUUGGACUUAGGGUAGGCAGUAAAAGUCAUUAAAGGUUUUUGAGCAACAAUAAUGGUAGUGAAACUAAUUCACAAAGAUUAGUCCAGUAGCACUGAGUAACAUAAAUGGCAGUGGGGGAUGUUUCAAAGUGGCAAGUUUGCUAAGACAACUGAUGUUAACCAGGUAAGAGAAUGAGAGCAUGAACAAAGAGCAAUGGAAAUAGACUGACAAAGAAGUUGAGGUAAGUUGUGAAAGCAUAAUUGACAAAUAUUUGGAUAUAUGAAGAAUGAGGAAGAGAGAGUAGAUUAAUCAAAAUUACUGUGUGAGAGGAUGGUGAUGCCACUGGUAAUAGGAAGAGAAGAUUUAGAGGGAAGAUUUGGACAUAGUUGAAGAUGCUGGUAGCACAUUGAAGCAUUGUGUCUUGCGCAUAUAGCUUUACAAAAUGGCCAUUGUGCUGGAUAUUCUUUUUGCCCUUCCUGAUCUAUUUUCCAUCUUUAUCUCUCUUGUUCUGUGUUCCUGGGAGGCUGACAAAUAAAGAACUGCAUACUCUCUUUUCUGGCUUUAUUCAUGGUGGGUUUGGACAGUGAUAGAAAAGUGAGGCUGAAAUAUUUGCUCCUUCUCUUUCUCAUAUACUUAGCAAGAGAUUGUGAGUGGCCACAGCUCUGCUCCAGUGGCCCUCUUAUAGCUCUAGGUCUUUUCUGGCUUCUCGUAACUGUCUCCUAUUGCUAGAUUCUCUAGUCCCAAGAAGGUUCAAACCUUGUUGAUUUGCCUUAACUGUGCCCAUACCCUUGUAAAUAGUUCCUUUUAUUAAAACUCUUCAAUAACUGAAUAUACUGUGGUCAUCUCUUCAGUGAAAUUAAAAAAAAAAACUUCUUUCACAUUUUCUUAUGACUUGAUCUUCCCACACCACCAAACGUGAAGAUCUAGCUAUUUGCACUAGGUUACUAUCCCUAAAUUCAGUGCCUCCCUGUUUCUUAGUAUGUCAAGUUAAAAUUUGUUACUCUUCUGCUGGGUGAUUGUGCUGGAAAUACAGAAGAAAAAGACAAAAAUCCCUGCCCUCAAAGAGCUUAUAUUUUACUGGGGAGAGACAGGCAAUAAGACAUAAUCAAUUAUAUGGUAUGUUAGAAGAUGAGAAGUAUAGAAAAAAUUAGGGUGAGGAAUGGCGAUUGUUGCAAGGGAUGUUUGUGAGGAUAGCAUACUUUAAAAUAGGUGGUAUGGGUAGGUCUCUCAGAAAGUGACAUUUGAGCAAAGACUUGAAGGAAAUGUGGGAGUGAGCAAUAUAGGUAUGGGAAGAGCAUUCUAGGUAGAGGAUUAGGAAGAGCAAAAGCCCUGAAGCAGGACUGUGUCUGGCCUCUGAAGAAAUGCAAAUUGUUCAGGGUUGUUGGACCUGAAGGAAGAGGAGGAAAGGAAUAAUGAGGCCAGAGGGGCCAGAUCAUGUAGGGAUUUGUAGGUUGUUGUAAGGAUUUUGGUUUUCACUAAAUGAAUGGUGAACCAUUUCAGUUUUGAGCAGAGGAGUUCCAUGAUCUGAUUUGAAUUUUAAAAGAUGUGUUUCCCAAAAUUCCUAUUCCUUUCAUACAGCUGCUUUCAAUGAAGGUUUAUAAGGAAAGCAAUCAGAACUACUUGGAUAAGGUAUAAGUGAUCCACAAUCUUUUCAACUCUACCAUAGGUAUCUACAUAUAUAUGUUGAGAGAUGCUGCUUUUUGGCCAAAAUGAAUCUUGAAUUGGGGGUGUGCAGAAAAAGUUAUAUCUGGCCUGAGGCUGGUAUCUUUUAGAGUGGCCUACUUGCAUGGUUGGCCCUUAUCUGAACACGUGGAUUUAGGGGUAUUCUCACUGUUCACUAAUAAAGGUGGUUCACUGUACCUAGACUGUUCAAACAAGAUGAUUUAUGCUAAACACCUGCUUUCCUUCUGGGAGUAUGGAAUUUUGGUACAUGCCAGGUAAAGGAUGUCUAUAUGACCAAACUCCCAAUGAAAACCUUGCAUACUGAGUCCCUAGGCAGAAACAUCCCUCGUAUAAAAAUGUGCUCUGUGUGAAUCUUCAUGGGAGGGAGAGAUCCUAAAGAAGCCUGCACAUGGAUUCCUCCAGAUUCUGCUUAUGUCUUUUUCCUGUAUGAUCCAACUGUGUACACUUACUGUGUCACUGUAAUAAACUUUAGCCAUGAGUACGAUA